AUCCGGGGUCACGUCGGUCUUCCGGGUGUCUUUGACAGGGUUUUCUACGCCGCUUUUUCGGCGACUUUUUGCUCUUCCGCUUUUUGCCACCGCCCCCAACCUUCUAUAUCCUUGCAGCCCCUACCUUUUCUUGUGUUGCUCCUCCCCUGGCAGCCGUGAGGGGGGUUAGAUCUCAGCCGGAGCCGGAGCUGGGCCUAGCUGUCCCACGGGCCACCACUACCUCCUUUGGUUCGGGAGAAAGCUACGACCAAGUACGCCCAGCUCGGGCCUUAGAACUUCUGAACGGGCAGUGCGGGUAGGCCCUGCUUAGCCCUUCCCGGAGGACACCUGACCAAAAGAGGAAGAUAGUCUUGGGACCCUUGCAUGGUGUUUCAAAGGGUGGUGAAGAACUAAGGUAUAUUCUGCUUUCUAAAGAAUCCUGAUGAAGGAAUUAUAUAUAACCUUGAGUGUUCUCUAAUUUGUUGGAGGAGAGGUCAAGUUGAGGACAGAAAUUCCAGGUUGCAAAUUCCAGGACCAAAUACUUUAUAACUAGAAAUUACUAGGAAUUAAUCUUUUUUUUUUUUUUUUUUUUUUUUUUUGCAAGACGGAAUCUUGAUCUUGUCACCCAGGCUACAGUGCAAUGGCACUAUCUUGGCUCACUGCAGCCUCUGCCUCCUGGGUUCAAGCGAUCUCCUGCCUCAGCCUGCCGAGUAGCUGGGAUUACAGGCACGUGCCACUAUGCUUGGCUAAUUUUUGUAUUUUUAGUAGAGGCAGGGUUUCACCAUGUUGGCCAGGCUGGUCUCCAACUCCUGACCUCAGGUGAUCCAUCCGCCUCGGCCUCCCAAAGUGCUGGGAUUACAGGCGUGAGCCACUGUGCCCGGCCGAAUUAAUCUACUCUUUUACUACCUUGUCUCAUGUAAACCUGUGUAAUUUCCCAUUGGGUCCACCUUAGGAAACCGUCUUUAAGGUUUUCUCCGUAAAGAAAGUACCAGUAUACUCUUUCAUGGUCAAGUACAGAUUGUGGAACUGAUAACUUUUAAGGUAGAAGAAUACAUGUUCACUUCCAGUGAACAAGAGCAUGUUCCCAAACUCAAUUUUGGGUCGCCCACCCUUCACUCCAAAUCAUCAACAACAUAAUAACUUCUUUACCCUGUCACCUACUGUUUAUUCACACCAGCAGCUUAUAGAUGCACAAUUCAACUUUCAGAAUGCAGACUUGUCUAGAGCUGUGUCAUUACAGCAGCUGACAUAUGGAAAUGUCAGUCCAAUACAGACCUCAGCUUCCCCAUUAUUUCGAGGAAGGAAGAGAUUAAGCGAUGAAAAAAACCUUCCUCUUGACGGUAAACGGCAACGUUUCCAUUCACCCCACCAAGAGCCAACUGUAGUUAACCAGAUAGUGCCUUUAUCAGGUGAACGAAGAUACUCAAUGCCACCAUUGUUUCAUACACAUUAUGUACCAGAUAUAGUCAGAUGUGUUCCACCUUUUCGAGAAAUUGCAUUUUUAGAACCUAGAGAAAUCACACUGCCUGAGGCCAAAGAUAAGUUGAGUCAGCAGAUACUGGAGUUAUUUGAAACAUGUCAGCAGCAAAUAAGUGAUUUAAAGAAGAAAGAACUCUGUCGAACACAGCUGCAGAGAGAAAUUCAGCUGUUAUUUCCACAAAGCAGACUUUUUUUGGUUGGGUCCUCUUUAAAUGGAUUUGGUACCCGGAGCAGUGAUGGUGAUUUAUGCCUAGUUGUUAAGGAAGAACCAUGUUUUUUUCAGGUAAAUCAGAAGACUGAAGCACGGCAUAUACUCACCUUAGUCCAUAAACACUUCUGUACUAGACUUUCGGGCUACAUUGAGAGACCUCAGCUGAUUCGAGCAAAAGUGCCAAUUGUGAAGUUCAGGGAUAAAGUCAGUUGUGUGGAGUUUGACUUGAAUGUAAACAAUAUUGUUGGAAUAAGAAACACAUUCCUUCUCAGAACUUAUGCAUACCUUGAAAAUCGAGUUCGUCCGUUAGUGCUGGUGAUUAAGAAGUGGGCAAGUCACCAUCAGAUAAAUGAUGCCAGUCGUGGUACUUUAAGCAGCUAUAGUCUUGUAUUGAUGGUUUUGCACUAUUUACAAACCCUACCUGAACCCAUCCUUCCAUCCCUCCAAAAAAUUUACCCAGAGUCUUUUAGUCCUGCUAUACAGCUGCACCUUGUACAUCAAGCUCCAUGUAAUGUUCCUCCUUACCUCUCAAAGAAUGAAUCAAACCUUGGGGACCUCUUACUGGGCUUUCUUAAAUAUUAUGCUACAGAAUUUGACUGGAAUAGUCAAAUGAUUUCAGUUCGUGAAGCCAAAGCCAUUCCAAGGCCUGAUGGUAUUGAAUGGAGAAAUAAAUACAUCUGUGUAGAAGAACCUUUUGAUGGAACAAAUACAGCCAGAGCAGUGCACGAAAAGCAGAAAUUUGAUAUGAUCAAGGAUCAAUUUUUAAAGUCAUGGCACAGAUUGAAAAACAAGAGAGAUUUGAACAGUAUACUACCUGUAAGAGCUGCUGUCCUGAAAAGAUAACUGGCCUCUAUUUCUUAAUAAAUUCUUCCAAGAAAUAAAGAACAAUAGUUUCAUCAUAAUACAUUAUGUUUACCUCCAUCAUAGUUGCUUUUUUCAUAGUUCUUGUUUUCAUGUUUUAUUUUUAAAAAGACAUAUAAAGAUUGCAUAUUUUAUUAUGACAUUUCCUAAUAAACCCCUUUGAUUUAAAAAUGUAUUUUUAAAAAUGUUUACAUUGAUGAUGAGUAAUAUUGCAUGUGUUUUCAGGUGAUCAGAUAAAAUAUAUUUUGGGAAAUUAACUGAACAAAUAAAAAGUUUUUGAUAUAACUUCAAUUAAUUGUACCACAUGCUAAUCCUGAAGAGAUGUGUAGAAUUUUGGAAAGGGUCUAAUUCAUACAUGCUUAAAGUAUAACCUACGUUAGAUAGUUUGUUGUCAAAGUCUGUUCUAGUAAAGUGAAGAUUCAAGUCAGUUGUUCAGUUACUUGAAGCAAAACGAAAUCUUUCAUUUCAGUCAAAUCACUGCAGUCAUGAAAUACUGAACAAUUGCCUUAAGUCUUUGCUUGACUCACUGGGAUAGACUGAGGCUUUGGGUGUGUCUGUAUUAGCAUUUCAUUAGUACUUCACAUGCUUUUGAUGUACUCUUGAGAUUGCUUUAAAUUUUGUAUUGAAACAACAAUACAUUUUGCACUGUAGUAAUGGGAGCACUAACUCUUACAACAGUUAGUGAAUCGUUUUAAAGAAUCAGUUCAGUGUAGACAUUUUGAAAAGAUUGUUUCCUGUGCUUUACGAUAGCUUAGUGCAAUGUGCACUUCUGUUUUACUUGCCAUUUUCCUGCUCUGUUUUCUCUGUGACAUGAAGCAACAGAAACUGAGAUCAAAGUUAAGAUUAUAUCCUGUUUGUAGUAUCAGAUAUUUUUCUGUGUACAAUUAUAGGAUUGUAAUCUAAACUGGAAUUUUUAGGCAGUAAGUCACCACAAAAUGUUUUAGAUAAGACACAAUAAAAUUAUUAUAAAUAAAAGCUUAAUGUUUGUAAAAAAUCUCUUUUUUAGUAUUUCUUUUUUCACAUGAAAGAAGUGGUGGCUGCUAAAAAAAAAGCUACAGUGUUUAUUAAGGGUCUUUUUGAUUUAUGUAAAUAUUUGUAAAUUGGUCAGUGCCUGUAAAUUUAAAUAUAAAAAGUAACCUUGAAAACAGUUUUAACUUUUUCAAAAGAACUAUGUCCAACAUUUUUUAGACCUGCUGUAGUACAGUUUUGUACCUCUAACGUAUUUUUUUUUUGCAGACCAAAUGCUAAAACUUUUGCUUUUCUUUGACUUGUAAAAGGUGCACAUUUUCAUUUUCUUCCUUAAGUUCAAAUUUUUGUAUGAUGUCAAAUGCAAUAAAAUUUAUAUAUGGACAUUGUUGAGGUGCCUUUUUUUUCUGUGAAAAUCUUUGCUUUGAGAUGAGACCGAGGCUGUAGUUAUCAUCUAGAACUGAACUAAAUCUACUUAUUAGCCAGCUAACGACAUCAAUAUCUUAUGUCUCUGGCAUUAUGAGGAAUGAAAGUUUACACAUAGUGAAUUUUUUAGAUUCCUGAUGUGUAACACUUUUUAUGCAUUUGAGCUUUUCAUAUUUUGGGGGGGAAUUUUUCCUAAAAUUUACACUGUGCAUCUCUUAAUCAGAAUGUACUGAGUAGAGUUAAUAUUCUAGUGAUGACUGGGUAAUCAUUAUAAGCAUUAGUCAUAGUACUAUUCAGUAAUACUGUGCAACUUUCAGGGAUGGGUAAGUAUGUACCCUCUGCCUCUACAGUAUUAUGACAUUUCCUAAUAAAACCCCAGAAUUUACCAUGGUGUGGGUUCCUUCACUGUCACUGUUUUCUCAGUUUUCAGUGGCCCCACACUUACUACUGCUUUUCUUUGUUUUACCACGAAAAACAGAUCAAGAAGUCACUAAACUUAGACCCAAUUCUAUAUCAGUAGACUGAGGCCUGAAAUUAUGCACACAUAACUGGCCAAAUAUCAGAUAAGUGAACUGUUAAUAUAUGAGAGAAUUUUCUGGACUUUUAAGUUAUUAAUCUCAAUUAUUUGUGUGGUGAGUACUAAAUUAUUUUCUGUUUGUGUUGAUCUGUCCAUUUCUGUAUAUAGUUGUCCCUCAGUAUAUUGAGGGAUUGAUUCCAGGUCAACCCCGUCCUCUUCAGAUACCAAAAUCCACAGAUACUCAAGUCCCUUAUAUAAAAUGGUGUAGUGUUUGCAUAUAUCCUACACACAUUCUCUUGAUACUUUAAAUCAUCUCUAAAUUACCUGAUACGUAAUACAAUGUAAAUGCUAUGUAAAUAGUUGUUAUACUGUAUUGUUUAGGGAAUAAUAAUGACAAGACAAAAAGUCUAUACCUGUUCGGUACAGAUGCAACCAUUCUGCCUCCUCCCUACCCCCUCCCAAAUAUUUUUCAUCCUGGUUGAAUUCACAAAUCCUACAUGGUUACGGAGGGUUGACUGUAUUUGCAUAUGUUGUUAAAGUGGUGUUUAAAAUGUGCAAUCUGUACUACAAUUCUAAAUUUUGGAUUGAUUUGAACUAGGAUCUUUGCAAAUAAAUCUCAUAGACAUUAAUGUUUGUAAGAAAUUUUUAAUUAAAUGAUGGAAGGAACAUAGAAUGGCUACCUGUGAUUUUGAUUAGUGUUUAACAGAUUGCCACAGCUGUGAUUGAAUUCCUUUUGUACUGGAUGAGCAUGGUCAUUUGGGAUUACUGAUGGUGAAGUCUAGCUGGUGUUAAGAGAAUAAAUAUUGCUGAUGCUAAACCUGGUUUAGUGAGCUGUGGAAGCCUUGACUCUGCUGUUUUCCCUCCUUAUGCCCCACUAGCUGAUGUAUCUGUACUGUAAUUCAAUGAUUUACAGUUCAUUACCUCCAGACAUAAUGCAUGCAUACCAGCUCGUGUAACUGGUGAAUAAUCCCCAGCUUACAGUCAUAUUUAACAACUCUGUGACUUGCUAUAAUUAAAAAUAAAUGUUAACUCUUCUAGCCAUCAAA